GAGAAGCCCGGAUCGAAGCGCAGGGUGGCAGCCCCGGAGCCGGGGAAUGUGAAGAGCUCUCGGCUGUGCAGUGGUACCGUCGGGGCCUGGGCCGCGAAGGAUCUUCUGCCACAGCUGCAACAUGGGCGGCAAGAACAAGAAACACAAGGCUCCAGCGGCCGCGGUGGUCCGGGCCGCCGUGUCUGCUUCCAGAGCCAAAUCUGCCGAGGCUGGAAUUGCCGGGGAGGCCCAAAGCAAGAAGCCAGUGUCCAGGCCGGCCACCGCUGCCGCUGCCGCUGCCGGCUCCAGGGAGCCCCGUGUCAAGCAAGGUCCAAAAAUUUAUAGUUUUAAUUCUACAAAUGAUUCUAGUGGUCCUGCAAAUCUGGAUAAAUCUAUUUUGAAAGUGGUAAUUAAUAACAAACUAGAGCAAAGAAUUAUUGGAGUGAUCAAUGAGCAUAAAAAGCAAAAUAAUGACAAAGGAAUGAUUUCUGGAAGACUUACUGCCAAAAAAUUGCAGGAUUUAUACAUGGCUUUACAAGCAUUUUCAUUUAAGACAAAGGACAUUGAAGAUGCCAUGACCAAUACACUCUUAUAUGGAGGUGACCUUCAUUCUGCCUUGGAUUGGCUCUGUUUAAACCUUUCAGAUGAUGCACUUCCUGAAGGAUUCAGUCAGGAAUUUGAAGAGCAGCAACCUAAAAGUAGGCCUAAAUUUCAGUCUCCUCAAAUACAAGCCACUAUUUCACCUCCAUUGCAACCUAAAACAAAAACAUAUGAAGAGGACCCUAAGAGUAAGCCAAAAAAGGAAGAAAAAAAUAUGGAAGUAAAUAUGAAAGAGUGGAUUUUACGAUAUGCUGAACAACAAAAUGAAGAAGAAAAGAAUGAGAAUUCUAAAAGUUUAGAAGAGGAGGAAAAAUUUGACCCUAAUGAAAGGUACUUACAUCUUGCAGCAAAACUGCUGGAUGCAAAAGAACAAGCAGCUACCUUUAAACUAGAAAAAAACAAGCAAGGCCAAAAAGAGGCUCAGGAAAAAAUAAGGAAAUUUCAAAGAGAAAUGGAAACUUUAGAAGACCAUCCAGUAUUUAACCCAGCCAUGAAGAUUUCACAUCAACAAAAUGAAAGGAAAAAGCCUCCUGUAGCCACAGAAGGAGAAAGUGCAUUGAAUUUUAAUUUAUUUGAAAAAUCUGCAGCUGCUACUGAAGAAGAGAAAGAUAAAAAGAAAGAACCUCAUGAUGUAAGAAAUUUUGACUAUACUGCUCGAAGUUGGACUGGAAAAUCUCCCAAACAAUUUCUGAUUGAUUGGGUCAGGAAGAAUCUUCCCAAGAGUCCAAAUCCUUCCUUUGAAAAAGUUCCAGUAGGUAGAUACUGGAAAUGUAGGGUUAGGGUAAUCAAGUCUGAAGAUGAUGUCCUGGUAGUAUGCCCUACAAUCUUAACAGAAGAUGGCAUGCAAGCUCAGCACCUGGGAGCUACUUUAGCCCUUUACCGUUUAGUUAAAGGGCAGUCAGUUCAUCAGUUACUUCCUCCCACUUACCGAGAUGUUUGGCUGGAGUGGAGUGAUGCAGAAAAGAAAAGGGAAGAAUUAAAUAAAAUGGAAACCAAUAAACCACGUGAUCUUUUUAUUGCCAAACUUCUGAAUAAACUGAAACAGCAGCAACAGCAGCAACAACAGCAUUCUGAAAAUAAGAGAGAAAACUCUGAAGAUCCCGAGGAAUCUUGGGAAAAUUUAGUUUCGGAUGAGGAUUUUUCUGCACUGUCCUUGGAAUCAGCAAAUGUGGAAGAUUUGGAACCUGUUAGAAACCUCUUUAGAAAGUUGCAAAGCACACCUAAGUAUCAGAAACUUCUAAAGGAAAGACAACAGCUACCUGUAUUUAAACAUCGGGACUCAAUUGUUGAAACUCUUAAAAGGCAUCGGGUAGUGGUUGUGGCAGGUGAAACAGGGAGUGGUAAAAGUACUCAGGUACCACAUUUUCUAUUGGAAGAUUUGCUUCUAAAUGAGUGGGAAGCAAGUAAAUGUAACAUUGUCUGUACCCAACCCCGAAGAAUCUCAGCAGUUAGUUUAGCCAACAGAGUAUGUGAUGAAUUGGGCUGUGAAAAUGGACCUGGAGGAAGGGUAAGCUGUCAUUCAACUCCACCUCAGUGAAUGAUGGUGACAUUACUCACCUUUGCUUUUGUGAUCCAAAUGGAAUGUGUACCAUAUAAUUCCUUGUGUGGAUAUCAGAUCCGGAUGGAAUCUCGAGCUUGUGAAUCUACCAGGUUACUCUAUUGUACAACAGGGGUUUUGCUAAGGAAACUUCAAGAAGAUGGUCUUCUAAGUAAUGUGUCUCAUGUUAUUGUAGAUGAGGUUCAUGAAAGAAGUGUCCAGUCAGACUUCCUACUAAUUAUCUUGAAGGAAAUUUUACAGAAACGUUCUGAUCUACACUUGAUUCUAAUGAGUGCCACUGUGGACAGCGAAAAAUUUUCUACAUAUUUCACACACUGCCCCAUUCUCAGAAUUUCAGGAAGAAGUUAUCCUGUUGAGGUUUUUCAUCUUGAAGAUAUAAUAGAAGAAACAGGCUUUGUACUGGAAAAAGACUCAGAAUAUUGUCAGAAAUUUCUGGAAGAGGAAGAAGAAGUAACCAUUAAUGUUACAAGCAAAGCAGGGGGAAUAAAAAAAUAUCAGGAAUACAUCCCAGUUCAGACUGGAGCACAUGCUGAUUUAAAUCCAUUUUACCAAAAGUACAGCAGCCGCACUCAGCAUGCUAUUCUAUACAUGAAUCCUCAUAAAAUCAACCUGGAUCUCAUUUUGGAACUUCUUGCAUACUUAGAUAAAAGUCCCCAAUUCAGAAAUAUUGAAGGAGCAGUAUUGAUCUUUUUACCAGGACUUGCUCAUAUUCAGCAGUUGUAUGAUCUUCUAUCAAAUGAUAGAAGAUUUUAUUCUGAACGAUAUAAAGUGAUAGCUCUGCAUUCUAUUCUUUCAACCCAAGAUCAAGCUGCAGCAUUCACACUUCCCCCUCCAGGAGUCAGGAAGAUUGUUUUAGCAACCAAUAUUGCAGAGACGGGUAUCACUAUUCCUGAUGUUGUAUUUGUAAUUGAUACUGGAAGAACAAAAGAAAAUAAGUACCAUGAAAGCAGUCAGAUGAGUUCUUUGGUGGAGACGUUUGUCAGUAAAGCCAGUGCUUUGCAGCGCCAGGGAAGAGCUGGGCGGGUCAGAGAUGGCUUCUGUUUCCGAAUGUACACAAGAGAAAGAUUUGAAGGCUUUAUGGAUUAUUCUGUUCCUGAAAUCUUACGUGUACCUUUGGAGGAAUUAUGCCUUCAUAUUAUGAAAUGUAAUCUUGGUUCUCCUGAAGAUUUCCUCUCCAAAGCCUUAGAUCCUCCUCAGCUCCAAGUGAUCAGCAAUGCAAUGAAUUUGCUCCGAAAAAUUGGAGCUUGUGAAUUAAAUGAGCCUAAACUGACUCCGUUGGGCCAACACCUUGCAGCUUUACCUGUGAAUGUCAAGAUUGGCAAGAUGCUUAUUUUUGGUGCCAUAUUUGGCUGCCUUGACCCAGUGGCAACACUAGCUGCAGUUAUGACAGAGAAGUCUCCUUUUACCACACCAAUUGGUCGAAAAGAUGAAGCAGAUCUUGCAAAAUCAGCUUUGGCCAUGGCGGAUUCAGACCACCUGACGAUCUACAAUGCAUAUCUAGGAUGGAAGAAAGCACGACAAGAAGGAGGUUAUCGUUCUGAAAUCACAUACUGCCGGAGGAACUUUCUUAAUAGAACAUCACUGUUAACCCUAGAGGAUGUAAAGCAGGAGUUAAUAAAGUUGGUUAAGGCAGCAGGAUUUUCAUCUUCCACAACUUCUACCAGCUGGGAAGGAAACAGAGCCUCACAGACCCUCUCAUUCCAAGAAAUUGCCCUUCUUAAAGCUGUACUGGUGGCUGGACUGUAUGACAAUGUGGGGAAGAUAAUCUAUACAAAGUCAGUGGAUGUUACAGAAAAAUUGGCUUGCAUUGUGGAGACGGCCCAAGGCAAAGCACAAGUACACCCAUCCUCAGUAAAUCGAGAUUUGCAAACUCAUGGAUGGCUCUUAUACCAGGAGAAGAUAAGGUAUGCCAGAGUGUAUUUGAGAGAAACUACCCUAAUAACCCCUUUUCCAGUUUUACUUUUUGGUGGUGAUAUAGAAGUUCAGCACCGAGAACGUCUUCUUUCUAUUGAUGGCUGGAUCUAUUUUCAGGCCCCUGUAAAGAUAGCUGUCAUUUUCAAGCAGCUGAGAGUUCUCAUUGAUUCAGUUUUAAGAAAAAAGCUUGAAAAUCCAAAGAUGUCCCUUGAAAAUGACAAGAUUCUGCAGAUCAUUACGGAAUUGAUAAAAACAGAGAAUAACUGAAACUGAAAUUCAUGGUCAACUGCUUUAAAAAUUAAGAUGAAGAUACAGUCAUGAAAUUAUCUGAAAAUGGGUCAUCACAUUAAGUAUUUCAUUACUUAAAAUGUUGGUACUAGCCAUUAACUUAAAGGUGGUGGGAAAAAAGCACAUACUUUAAACAUGUAUAAUUUUCUAGUUCCUUUUUAAUGAUGAUUAUUCUGAAUGUAUUUGCCACUACAUUUACAAUAAAUUCUUUGGUAUUAUGCAUGUUUUGCUCAUCGUUGUGUUAAUAAGGGCAAGGCCUAUGUCUGUGGUAUCUGUAGCUUAAUGUUGUGAUUCCCUGUGUAGCUGCCUCAUCCCCUAUCAGUCCUUGAUGUCUGCAGAAUUUAAACCCUAUAGACCCAGAAGGGAAAAUAAUCUCCAAAACCAAUUAUAAUUAAAUUUCCAUGAAAAGGAA